AUUUGAAGAGCACCUACUGCAGAGUUAGGCUUAACUCCACCCAACAGCCAAGUCUGAAACCACUGACGGUACCAUGAGGGCUUUCAUUUUCUUUCUCUUCAUGCUCCUGGCCAUGUUCUCAGCAUCUUCAACCCAGAUUUCAAAUACCAGUGUUUUCAAACUAGAAGAGAAUCCAAAACCUGCACUUAUUCUGGAGGAAAAAAAUGAAGCUAACCAUCUAGGAGGACAAAGAGAUUCUAAUAAGCAAGGAGGUAGUUAUACACAAGGAAAUCCAGGAACGUUUAGGCUUCAAGGACAACCAGGCUAUUUUAACAAGCUAGAGAAACCAAGACAUUUUAAGCAAGGGAGAGCAGGAGUUUUAAACCAGCCUGGGAUUUUAAAGAAUUCAGGAAAAUCUAACCAAAAAGGGAAUCCAGAAUCUUCUAAUAAGCAGGAAAACUCAGGAUCUUCUAGCCAACUAGGGAGACCAGGGAUUUCUACCCAACAGGGAAAUCCAGGGUCAUCUGACCAACAAGAGAAACCAGGGUCAUUUAGCCAGAAAGUGAUGGUGGGGUCAUCUAGCCAACAGGGGAAGCCAGGAUCAUCUAGCCAACACGGGAAUCUAGGGUCAUCAACCCAGAAAGGGAAUUUAGGAUCUUCUAGCCUACAAGGGCAUCUGGGUUUAUCUAGCCAUCAAGGGAAGCCAGAGUCAUCUGGCCAACAGGGGAAGCCAGGGUCAUCUAGCCAACAAGGAAAUCUAGGAACUUCUGGCCAACAGGAGAAGCCAGGAUCUUCUAGCCAACAGGGGAAGCCAGGGUUGUCUAGCCAUCAAGGGAAGCCAGGGUCAUCUAGCCAACAAGGAAAUCUACAUUUAUCUAGCCAGCAAGGGAAUCAAGGACCUUCUAGCAAACAGAGGAAGCCAGGUUCAUCCAGCCGUCAAGGAAAUCUAUGAUUAUCUAGCCAGCAAGGGAAUAUAGGAUCUCCUAGCCAACAGGAGAAGCCAGAGUCUUCUAGCCAACAAGGGAAUCUAGGGUCAUCUAGCUAUCAAGGGAAGCCAGUGUCAUCUAGCCAACAAGGGAAGCCAGUGUCAUCUAGCCAACAAGGGAAGCCAGGGGCAUCUAACCAGCAAGGAGAUCUAGGAUCUUCUAAGCAGCAGGGGAAGCCAGGAUCAUCUAGCCAGCAAGGAAAUAUAGGGUCAUCUGGCCAGGAAUGGAAGCCAGAGCCAUCUAGCCAUCAGAGAAAAUUAAGGUCAUUUUACAACCAACGACAAAGAAAAAA